ACAGGUGGGUGUGCCUCUGGCUGCUUUUAACAUCCUCCCUUUGCUGUUCUGAAAACUUCACGUCAGAGUCAUAUUUAAAUGUGUAAUUACUGCUCUUUCUCCUGCUUAUAAUUCAUUAUACUUUUUGAAUUUGAGGCUUGUGUUUUUAUGAACCUUGAAAAGCCCUCUGCUGCCGGCCUCUGGAGCCACCGUCUCCCUGCCCUGCUCUCUCCUCUGCCGAGGUGCCUGUUAAGCUGCAUUCUCUCCUCCACAGCUCCCCGCUUCCUGCAGGCUUCCUGUCUCACUUUCUUUCUGUGCUCCAGAGUCUAGGCAAUCUCUUUUGUUAGAACUUCCAAUUCACCAAUACUUUCUUAUGUUGUGUCUAAUAAGCUACAUCAUCUGCUCACUGGGUUUUUUAUUUCAGUGAUUAUAGUUUUCAUUUCCAGAUAUUCCAUAUGCCUUAAAAACAUCUGCAUGAUACUCCAUGGUUUUAACUCCCCUGAUGAAUACUGUGCAUUUAACCAUCCCAGCACGUGAGGUCCCUGGGGCUGACCCCUGCUGACCCUCUCAGAACAGCUUUCUUCCUCAACGUCUUGUAAUUCCAACCAGGCUCUUCGUCUGUCUACACUCUGGGAGCCGGAAGGCCGGGAUGAGGAAGGCUUUUCUAGCAAGAGUCUUUUAGGAGACACAGGCCACGAUACUGUCAACAUAGGAAAAUGUGCAACUCCUGCGUCCCACCGUAAAACUCGAAGACGUCAAAAUACAUUCUUGAUUCUGCUCCACAAAGGGAUGUUUCCAUGGCGAUAUUUUCAAACAACAGAAAGUUCACGGCCGAUGGCGGUUACAGCUCAUGGAACUGAUGGGCAGGGCCGGGUGCAGCUUUGUAGCACGGCUGCUGCUCACAGAUUCUCUUCCAUUUGACUAAAAACCAUGCUGUCCACACCAAACAUCUGGCCUCAUCCGGAUGUUCAAAGCCAUGAAAUACAGCACUUCUGGCCAAGAAGUCUAAAUCACAGCCGAUCUACACGAGGCGGAUGGUCCACAACGCCAAGUUCCUACCCGGGCACUGAGCUCAACGCUCGCACAACUCCAAACGAGGGCGCAACCAUAUUCCCACUGACAUCCUCCUUGGGGCAGCAAGACAAGCUCCGAACAGCCUGUCCUGGGCCAACAAGAGAAGCUGGCGGGCGCCCGCUGAGCACUGUGAGCCAUCUUGUGGUGAGACUGGCUUCUCCUUCCAAUCUCCAGGUUUCUCUCUCUUUCUGCCUUCUUUCUGUCAGUUACCGUCAUUGAUCACUUAAAGAAAGACAGGGCCUACCCCUGUCUGCUGCGUGACCUCAGCCCUCCCGCCUGCCGAUGGGAGCUGGGUCAUCUCUUACGCCUUUCAGCUUUGGCUUCUUCCGCAGUGUAUGUGAAGGGGUCACACAGAGGUAAGGCUGUGCGUCCAGCCCUUGCCUGCACAACCUCCAUGCCUUCCCCAUCUCCAGGCCGGGGUGGGGUAGGGGUAGGGUGGGGUGGGGCGGAAGGACCAGUUCCACAGGAAGCCUGUGGAGGCAAACAGGGUUAUGUGGCAAGGGUGGGAAGGAGCAGGGCCUGAGCCCCAUGGUGGUUUCACCAGCAUCCAGCGGUCACCAUGGUGAACAAGAAGCCAGGAAGGAAGGAAGCAAUGUCGGCAAAAGGGCUCAGAUGACAACCAAACAGAACGGUUUCCCACCCUGGGCCUCCUUUCCACACACACAGCAUCGUGGGUAUUUUAAAAUAAACAAGAUCAACGUCCAAACCUGCGCUGAGGCCUGAGCUGUGUCCGUCACUCCUGCAGGGCACAGGCCUGCCUGGCCGAAUGCAUGGGCGGUGAGAGCACAGGGCUGGGGGGACCCCUCUGUCGAGGGGCCACAGCUCCUCACACAGCAGAGCUUUAUGGAUGAAAGGGCUGAGAGGCACAGACAGGCUGAGAAAUGGGCCCAAAGUCCCACAGCAUGGAGCCAGGAGGUAGCAGACGGCCCCUGCCCGCCCCCCUCACUUGGCUGACUGCUCCCACGGCAGCCACCACCUUUAUCCUGAGUCCCGGGGUCCUCCAUCAAAUCGCUGAGCCUCGGGUGGUCUUGUGGACCCCAGCUUGUCUGUGUUGUGUUGACAACAUGGGCCUGGCUACCGGCCUAAGUGCACUUCUGAGGGGUGUCAGGGAAGCCUUUGCUGCGGCUUGGGGAUUACAGAAUUUUAAACAGCAAGAACCUUCCCUUUGCUAGUCCAAGCUUCCCUUUGUAUGAGAAACUGCUUACGUCUAGAGAGGAAAAAUGGUUGAGAAAUAGGAGGACCAGAGACCAAUCACGCGGAGUUCUUAAUCAUGUGAAAAUAUUUUAUUUUGACGUGCUUUUUCUUGAGUGCCUGAAUGUGGUGGCUCUUAGGGUAACCCCAGAAUCCUCACUGCGGCAACAAGACCUGGCCACCACCCUCACCUCGACCACCACGGCCUUCGCUGCAGCCCCACUCUGACUCCCCGGGGGCUGCUCACGUGCCAGCACCCACUGGCCAAGCAUCCUCCGGCAGGACCCAAGUCCUCUGUAUUCAGAGGCCGACCCUGCUUUCCAGAGACUCACGAGGUGGCAGAGAGUCAGGCUGUGGCAGGGGCCCCUGUGUAUCGAGGAGAGGAGGAAGAGUCUGCAGAGGUUUCUAGGGAAGGAGAUAGUGUGGAAGUGACUGUGGCUCUGGUCCUGCCUGGGAGGAGAUCUACAGGGGAGGGGCCUGGCCUUGGGCUGGCCCUGCCCUGCGUGGGAUCUGUGCCCUGCGUGGGAUCCCUGCCCUGUGUGGGGUGCGUGGGGUCUGUGCCCUGUGUGGGGUGCCUGCCCUGUGUGGGGUGUGUGGGGUCUGUGCCCUGUGUGGGGUGCCUGCCCUGUGUGGGAUGCAUGGGGUCUGUGCCCUGUGUGAGGUGCCUGCCCUGUGUGGGGUGUGUGGGGUCUGUGCCCUGUGUGGGGUGCGUGGGGUCUGUGCCCUGUGUGGGGUGCUUGGGGUCUGUGCCCUGUGUGAGCUGCCUGCCCCGUGUGGGGUGCGUGGGGUCUGUGCCCUGUGUGGGGUGCCUGCCCUGUGUGGGAUGCAUGGGGUCUGUGCCCUGUGUGAGGUGCCUGCCCUGUGUGGGGUGCGUGGGGUCUGUGCCCUGUGUGGGAUGCCUGCCCUGUGUGGGGUGCCUGCCCUGUGUGGGAUGCGUGGGGUCUGUGCCUUGUGUGGGGUGCCUGCCCUGUGUGGGGUGCGUGGGGUCUGUGCCCUGUGUGGGGUACCUGCCCUGUGUGGGCUGCGUGGGGUCUGUGCCCUGUGUGGGGUGCCUGCCCUGUGUGGGGUGUGUGGGGUCUGUACCCUGUGUGGGGUGCGUGGGGUCUGUGCCCUGUGUGGGGUGCCUGCCCUGUGUGUGGUGCAUGGGGUCUGUGCCCUGUGUGAGGUGCCUGCCCUGUGUGGGGUGUGUGGGGUCUGUGCCCUGUGUGGGGUGCCUGCCCUGUGUGGGAUGCGUGGGGUCUGUGCCCUGUGUGAGGUGCCUGCCCUGUGUGGGGUGCGUGGGGUCUGUGCCCUGUGUGGGGUGCCUGCCCUGUGUGGGGUGCGUGCGGUCUGUGCCCUGUGUGGGGUGCCUGCCCUGUGUGGGGUGCGUGGGGUCUGUGCCCUGUGUGGGGUGCCUGCCCUGUGUGGGGUGUGUGGGGUCUGUGCCCUGUGUGGGGUGCCUGACCUGUGUGGGGUGCGUGGGGUCUGCUACACGCUUGGUGAGAAACUGCAUCAGGGCUUCCCGCCGUGUGUUGCUAACAUCCCCACACACGUGAGUGCCUUGGGACCCUCGUCAACACACUGAGCUGAGGCCACUGGUCCACGGCACACUGCAGUGCACAUGCCCUUCCUGGCCAGAGGCUCCCAGGGGCGCCAUGCUCUCCAGGCACCUGCCCCGCCUGCGAGCACAGCCUGGCCCCUGCUGCACUCUGCUCUCUCUGCCCGCUCGGGUCCACUGCAGCUGAGCGGGUGGGAGAAGCCUCUUCAACUUCACACACUUGUCGCCUCUAGCACUGGGCAAGGUCUGGCAUUCAGAGUUCCAAGAAGUCCCACAGAUACCAGUGGCUAAGUCUGUCUUCCCUCCAGGAAUGGGGAAGCAGGAGCCGUCAGAACAGCCGUCUCCUAUCUGAGGCACCAGGAACAAACAUGACGUCAGGAAAAGACUGAAGGUGCCAAGCACCUAACGCUGAAGGAACCAGCAUGUGCCUGGCAGCACUGCAGAGAGCACACCCCAGGCACCAGAGACCAGGGUGUCAUUCACAGGUCAAAGCAAAAUAAGAAAAUCAUAAUUUUUCCCCUUGUUCCAAAGAAACAUCCACGUGCAGAGGGCAGGCAGCUUCGGCCCAUGGCGCUCCUGACGAGGGCUCCCUCGUGGCUGCCCCAGGACAAGCAGGACCCCGGCGGUCCUAGGCAGGGAGAAGCGAGACUCAG